UUCGAGGCUGCAUGAUUGCACCACUGUACUCCAGCCUAGGUGACAGAGCAAGACCUUGUCUCAGAAAAGCAAGACAAAGGGCAGGCUGUUCAGGAUGAUCAUGAUAGGUAUAGGGACUGCUGCAAUGGGAUUGUGUAGUGGGGGAGACCUAGGAGCAGGAGUGGGGGCCAUGGACGGAAAAUUUAACUAAGAGGAAACAUCAGGGUGCAGGGGGUUCUGGCUGAACUGACCUAACAGGAUUCUUGUGGAAGGCCGCUAGCAUCACUCCUCUGGACCAUAAACACUCGGGGAGUCCCAAUCUCUCCUGAGCAGUGCAUUGGCGCCAGCUUUCCAGAUGUGUGUGUAAGUCCAUCAUCCUUUAAGAAGUUUGCUUAGAAAGCCUAGAUGCUGAGACUUAAAAAUGGAGUCUCACCAUGGACAGUUCUCAUAAAGAAUUGUCUCCCAACAAAGUGGCUGACUGUGUUGUGGCUGUAUUGUUACAGACCUUCUCAGAUGUGUUUGCUGCAAGUUUUGUUUAUUUGGAACUCUUUGGAAGCUAGCACAACUACAUAGAAACCCAUAUAAGUUAGCCACCAUGCUCAGCUAAUUUUUAAAAAAAUUUGUUGUAGAGAUGGGGUCUCGUUCUGUUGCCCAGGCUGGUCUUGAACUCCUGGGCUCAAGUGAUCCUUCCACCUUGGCCUCCCAAAGUGCUGGGAUUACAGGUGUGAGCCUCUGUACUCAGCUAAUUUAGCUAGUUUUUGUAUUUGAUUUUUUUUUUUUUAAUAGAGUCUCUGUCAUCCCGGCUGGAGUGCAGUGGCACGAUCUCGGCUCACUGCAACCUUUGCCUCCCAGGUUCAAGUGAUUUUCUUGCCUCAGCCUCCCAAGUAGCUGGGACUAUAGGCAUGUGCCACCAUGCCCAGCUCAUUUUUGUAUUUUUAGUAGAGAUGGGGUUUCGCUAUUUUGGUCAGGCUGGUUUCGAAUUCCUGACCUCAGGUGAUCCUCCCACCUCAGCAUCCCAAAGAGCUGGAAUUACAGGCAUGAGCCAUAACGCCUGGCCCCAUAUGCUGUUUAUUUCAUUUUUCCCAAGCAAACUAGGACUUAGAGAUUGUUUCACAAAGCCCUGCUGACUCAUUUUCAACACUUCUCCACAGGACUAGUGCUAUGCGUCAGCAGACGCUGCCUGUGUGGGGAUGGAGGUUGGCUCAGACACAGUGCGUGGCCUCGGGAGCCUUACGUUCCAGCAACCACUUGACUAACAGUCAUAAAAAUUAAAAUUGUAAAAUAUUUUGUCAACUGUGCAUCAGCCAAACAAAAAAAAUUAAAAUUGCCUAAAGUGGAACAAGGAGAUGUGGGAUGAAGUCAAGCAAAUUAUGUGUCCAAAAAUGUAUAAUGUCAGUGAUUAGCUUCAGGAAGCAUUUGUAUUUAGUGCCUAUUGACAUCAGAGACAGCGCUAGUAGUUGGGGAUGCAGCAAGACGGGCCCCUGGCCCUUAAGGAACUUGUAGUCCAAAUGAACAACUGAAGUACUGCGGAGCUGAGCAGAGGGUGCUGUGUGAGGGUCCAGCAUGGACAAACUUAACCCCAGUGUGGGUGAGAUUCAUCAGGAAGGCUUUCUGGAGAAGGUGAUGUGGGCGAUGCAUGUUCUCCACCUAGCCAUGCCCAGAGGGAAGUGUGUCUGGGCAGAACUAUCAGGCUGGGGAGGACUCAGGGGUGGGAGAGAACCUGGCAUGCUGGGGAAGCUAAAUGUGGCGAUUGGUUUGUUUAUACAACUUGGAGUGCGGAAGGGGGUCAGUAAGGGGAUGCUGAUGCCUGAGGGUGAGGGUUGGGCAGAGGCAAUUUUAAGCAUGUGAGUCACAUGAUCAGAUUUCCAUUUUAGAAAGCUUGGAGAAUGGGUCUACUCAGGUAGCUCACACCUUGUGUUGUCCAUUUUCACACUGCUGAUAAAGUUGUACCCAAGACUGGGCAAUUUACAAAAGAAAGAGGUUUAAUUGGACUUACAGUUCCAUAUGGCUGGGGAAGCCUCACAAUCAUGGUGAAAGACAAGGAAGAGCAAGUCAUGUCUUACAUGGAUGGCAGCAGGCAAAGAGAGAAGCAUGUGUGCAGGGGAGCUCCUCUUUUUAAAACCAUCAGAUCUUGUGGGACUUAUUCGCUAUCAUGAGAACAGCACAGAAAAGACUUGCCCCCAUGAUUCAACUACCUCCCACCAGCUCCCUCCCAUAACAUGUGGGAAUUCAAGAUGAGAUUUGGGUGGGGACACAGCCAACCAUAUCAUUGUGCCCCUGCCCCCUCCCAAAUCUCAUAAUCAUGUUUCAAAACCAAUCAUGCCUUCCCAACAGUCCCCCAAAGUCUUAACUCAUUUCAGCAUUAACUUAAAAGUCCACAGUCCAAAGUCUCAUCUGAGAUAAGGCAAGUCCCUUCCAUGUAUGAGCCUGUAAAAUCAAAAGCGGGUUAGUUACUUCCUAAAUACAGUGGGGGUACAGGCAUUGGGUAAAUACAGCCAUUUCAAAUAGGAGAAAUUGGCCAAAACAAAGAGGCUACAGGCUCCCAUGUAAGUCUGAAAUCCAGCAGGACAGUCAAAUCUUAAAGCUCCUAAAUGAUUUCCUUUGACUGCAUGUCUCACAUCUAGGUUAUGCUGAUGGAAGAGGUGGGUUCCCAUGGUCCUGGGCAUCUCCGCCCCUGUGGCUUUGCGGGAUACAGCCUCCCUCCCAGCUGCUUUCACGGGCUGGCAUUUAGUGUCUGCAGCUUUUCCAGGUGCAUGGUGCAAGCUGUUGGUAGAUCUACCAUUCUGGGGUCUGGAGGACAGUGGCCAUCUUCUCACAGCUCCACUAGGCAGUGCCCCAGUAGGGACUCUGUGUGAGGCCUCCAGUGCCACAUUUCCCUUCCAUACUGUCCUAGCAGAGGUUCUCCAUGAGAGCCCCGCCCUUACAGCCAACAUCUGCCUGGACAUCCAGGCACUUCUGUAUAUUUUCUGAAAUCUAGGCGGAGGUUCCCAAACCUCAAUUCUUGACUUCUGUGCACUCUCAGGCCCAAUGCCAUGUGGAAGCUGCCAAGGCUUGAGGUACCCUCUGAAGCCAAGGCCCGAGUUCUGCAUUGGCCCUUUUCAGCCACGGCUGGAGCAGCUGGGAUGCAGGGCACCAAGUCCCUAUGCUGCACACAGAACAAGGACCCUGGGCCUGGCCCAUGAAACCAGUUUUUCCUUCUAGGCCUCUGGGCCUGUGAUGGGAGGGGCUGCCAUGAGGACUUCUGAAAUGCCCUGGAGACAUUUUCCCCAUUGUCUGGGGGAUUAACAUUAGGCUCCUCAUUACUUAUGCAAAUUUAUGCAGCCAGCUUGAAUUUCUCCUCAGGAAAUGGGAUUUUCUUUUCUUUUUUUUUCUUUUGAAAUGGAGUCUCACUCUGUCACCCAGGCUGGAGUGUAGUGGCACAAUCUUGGUUCACUGCAAUCUCUGCCUCCUGGGUUCAAACAAUUCUCCCGCCUCAGCCUCCUGAGUAGCUGGGAUUACAGGCGUGCACCACCAAGCCCGGCUAAUUUUCGUAUUUUUAGUAGAGACGGGGUUUCUCCAUGUUGGUCAGGCUGGUCUCAAACUCCUGACCUCAUGAUCCUCCUGCCUCAGACUCCCAAAGUGCUGGGAUUACAGGCAUGAGCCAUUGCUCCCGGCUGGGAUUUUCUUUUCUAUCACAUUGUCAGGCUGCAAAUUUUCCAAACUUUCAUUCUCUGCUUACUUUAUAAAACCGAAUGCUUUCAAUAGCACCCAAGUCACCUCUUGAAUGCUUUGCUACUUAGAAAUUUCUUCCACCAGAUACCCUAAAUCAUCUCUCAAGUUCAGAGUUCCACAAAUCUCUAGGGCAGGGGCAAAAUGCUGCCAGUCUCUUUGCUAAAACAUAACAAGUCACCUUUGCUCCAGUUCCCAACAAGUUCCCCACCUCCGAGACCUCCUCAGCCUGGACUUUACUGUUCAUAUAAUUAUCAGCAUUUUUGUCAAAGCCAUUCAACAAGUCUCUAGGAAGUUCCAAACUUUCCCACAUUUUCCUGUCUUCUUCUGAGCCCUCCAAACUGUUGCACCCUCUGCCUCUUACCCAGUUCCAAAGUCACUUCUACAUUUUUGGGUAUCUUUUCAGCAACACCCCACUCCUGGUACCAAUUUACAGUGUUAGUCCAUAUUCAUGCUGCUGAUAAAGACAUACCCAAGACUGGGCAGUUUUCAAAAGAAGGAGGUUUAAUGGAGUUACAGUUCCACAUGGCUGGGGAAGCCUCACAAUCAUGGCGGAAGGCAAGGAAAAGCAAAUUAUGUCUUACAUGGAUGGCAGCAGGCAAAGAGAGGAGAGCAUGUACAGGGGAAUUCCUCUUUUUAAAACCAUCAGAUCUCAUGUGAGACUUAUUCACUAUCAGGAGAACAACAUGGGAAAGACUUGCCCCCAUGAUUCAAUUACCUCCCACUGGGUCCCUCCCACAACACGUGGGAAUUCAAGAUGAGAUUUGGGUGGGGACACAGCUAAACCAUAUCACACCUGUAAUCCAGCACUUUGGGAGGCUGAGGCAGGAGAAUUGCUUGAGCCCAGGAAUUCAAGACCAGCCUGAGCAAUAUAGCAAGACUUCAUCUCUACAAAAAAUUUAAAAAGCCAGCAUGGUGGUGUGGGCCUGUAGUUCCUGCUGUUUAGGGGGCUGUGGUGGGAGCAUCUCUUGAGUUCAGGAAGUCGGGGCCCCAGUGAGCUAUGAUUGCAACAUUGCAGUCCAGCCUAGGUGACAGAACAAGAACCUGUCUCUAAAAAAGGGAGAAAAAAAGAAAGCUUGGAGAAUGGACUGGAAGAGGGAAGACUAGAGGCUCAUACAACCAGACACCAUUCGCUUUUCACCCAAGAUGAUUUGAUGUCUUAUAAAACUCUGAUGAACCAUGAUGGCUACACAGACAUUAAGUAUAGACAGCUAUCAAGAUGGGCAACAGAUGCAAGUAGUAACAGAGUUAAAGACAGAACAAGAUCCAAACUGCUCUGAACCCGAUGCAGAAGGAGUGAGCCCUCCCCCUGUGGAGUCUCAGACCCCGAUGGAUGUGGACAAGCAGGCCAUUUAUAGGCAUCCACUAUUUCCAUUAUUAGCUUUGUUGUUUGAAAAAUGUGAACAAUCUACACAGGGCUCUGAAGGCACAACUUCUGCCAGUUUUGAUGUAGACAUCGAAAAUUUUGUAAGAAAGCAAGAGAAGGAAGGGAAACCUUUCUUUUGUGAAGAUCCAGAAACUGAUAAUUUAAUGGUAAAAGCAAUCCAGGUUUUGCGCAUUCAUCUUCUUGAGCUGGAAAAGGUUAACGAACUCUGCAAAGAUUUCUGCAGUCGAUACAUUGCUUGUCUGAAAACAAAAAUGAACAGUGAAACUCUGUUGAGUGGAGAGCCUGGAAGCCCGUACUCACCAGUGCAGUCCCAGCAGAUUCAAAGUGCCAUCACAGGCACCAUCAGCCCUCAGGGAAUUGUGGUGCCGGCGUCCGCGCUGCAGCAGGGAAACGUAGCCAUGGCGACGGUGGCAGGUGGCACAGUGUAUCAGCCUGUCACGGUCGUCACUCCCCAAGGCCAAGUGGUCACACAGACAUUGUCGCCUGGGACAAUUAGGAUCCAGAACUCCCAGCUUCAGUUACAGUUAAACCAAGAUCUCAGCAUCUUGCAUCAAGAUGAUGGUUCAUCUAAGAACAAGAGGGGCGUCCUGCCAAAGCAUGCCACGAACGUGAUGCGGUCCUGGCUCUUCCAGCACAUCGGGCAUCCCUACCCAACAGAGGAUGAGAAAAAACAGAUUGCUGCUCAGACAAAUUUGACACUACUCCAAGUCAACAACUGGUUCAUCAAUGCCAGAAGACGAAUUCUUCAGCCAAUGUUGGAUUCAAGUUGUUCAGAGACCCCCAAAACAAAGAAAAAAACUGCUCAGAACCGGCCAGUUCAGAGGUUUUGGCCUGAUUCUAUUGCAUCAGGAGUCGCACAGCCACCGCCGAGCGAGCUCACCAUGUCGGAAGGAGCUGUUGUCACCAUCACCACGCCCGUGAACAUGAACGUGGACAGCCUUCAGUCUCUGUCCUCGGACGGGGCCACCCUGGCGGUGCAGCAGGUCAUGAUGGCAGGGCAGAGCGAGGACGAGUCUGUGGACAGCACAGAGGAGGAUGCGGGUGCCCUGGCCCCUGCCCACAUCAGCGGGCUGGUCUUGGAGAACAGUGACUCCCUGCAGUAGGGGCAGGAGCAGACGCACCUGACUUUUUGGAGUUUGCACAGCAAACAUUUUACACAGUUUUAUUUCUAAUAUGUUUUAUAUGUAGAUAUAGAAGAGUGCACUUUUGUAUUUCAUAGUAAGCUUAAAGCGCGUCUUUGCCGGUGCAGCGACUUCUUUCAAGUGUGUGUGUGUGUGUGUGUGUGUGUGUGUGUGCGUGUGUGCGUGUGUGUGGAUUUUUAAAGAAAUUCUUUAAAGGUUUAACGCUAGAUUGUGAGGAAUGACACACCACUCCCUCCCCACCUUGAAUCCCUAAUUAGAUUAAGGAAUAGCGCUGCCAUUUUCUAAACCGUGAUGCGGUUGUCACUUAGUUCUGUGGUUCCAGCAGAUCUCAGUGGGCUGGUUGAUUUGUGUGGCCCAUGGAUUUGAAAGAAGCUGCUGCACCCGAAACUGCCAGUGUGCGGUGACAACGGCACACGCCUAGACUGAGUGUGGUUUCGUCGUGAGUGGAUGGACGGCAAGCUUAGCAAGCCUAAGUCCCCUCAUGUUCAGUGAGCCUGUUUCAUUUGCUAUAUAGAAAAAGAAACUCCUAUUUUUACCUUGCUGGAAUUAUUGGAUAAAAAAGCUAUUUUUAUAAAUUCGUUAUGAAUUGGAUGAUGACUAUAUUGAGGAUAAAAUUUCUAGAGAAGAAACAAUACAUGCUUGCUAUUAAUAUUUCAAUUUGGAAUGUUCUGAAUUGACCAAAUUUAAUGAACCUGCCCAAAGUUAGCUACCGUUCCAUGGUUCUUUGCUCUCCCCGGGUAGUGAUGAACAUUUACUACUAUAAAAGAAACAGCUAUUUAAUGAAAUUUUGAUAUCUGCAAAUUUUUGUUGAUAUGUAAUGCUCAGAUUGCAUUUUACACUUGAUCUAAACAUAUAUCGAAAGAUAUCUGCUAAACAGGACUUCAGGUAAGUGAGGUGAAAUGGUAGCCAGUGACCCGUUAGGAGCUCUCACCGUACAUACUCCAGUCUAAUUUAAAUCUGACCACAGUUGCAUGGUCGCUUUACCAUGUUAGCUGUGUAUUGUUUUAAAAGUUUUAACUUCAAAAUAUGUUAUGCACAGAAUGUUUAUUAUAAACUAAUAUAAAAUGUGCUCUACCCCAUUGGCUCAGAGCUAGGGCAAACAGCAGAUAUUCAGACUUUAUUACUUAACUAGCGGACAUCCCUGGAGUCCCAGCAGCGAGCUGGUCUGGCGAGGGCACCUCGGCAGCCCCCACGGGUUGGCUCCUACGUUUGCGUUUGUGGCUGGUCUCCUGGUGUCAGUGUUCUCUUGUACGUUGUUGCUUUCGACUUUUCAGAGCCCUCCUGCUCACUUGACCACGUGAGAUUUGGAAUAACUGUAGGACUUCUGUUUCCUGGUAACAAGAUGAACCGAGAGAGUGGGCUGGGUUCUGUUUUCUUUGGUUUUGAUUUGUUUUCAUUGUUUACUUAGGAGUGGUGCUUUUUCUCAGAAAACAGGCCACGGUGUUUCAUACAGAAUGUCUUCAUAUCAUCUGAAAUGGUAUGGCUGAAGUUCAUUUGUUUACAGGGUCGGGAAUGUCUUCAGUUCUUGAGAGUCAACAGUAAUGAUUGGUUGUAAGCCAAGGGACAUUUUAAGCUAGUGAAGAGUUUUUUCUGGAAUUGAUUUUUCCCAAAAGAAUAUAUUAAUUGAGGUUAAGAAGUCAGUGGGAAACACACAGAAAUUUGUUUUAAAAUCUUUCAGGAGCUUUACUGAAAGACUUGGUUAUCAAGUCUUUUGGGGAGAGAAUGACAUUUUUUUUUUGAGACAGAGUUUUGCUCUUGUUGCCCAGGCUGGAGGGCAAUGGUGCAAUCUCAGCUCACUGCAACCUCCACCUCUUAUGUUCAAGCAAUUCUCCUUCCUUAGCCUCCUGAGUAGCUGGGAUUACAGGCAUGCGCCACCACACCCGGCUAAUUUUGUAUUUUUAGUAGAGAUGGGUUUCUCCAUGUUGGUCGGGCUGGUCUCGAACUCCCGACCUCAGGUGAUCUGCCUGCCUCAGCCUCCCAAAGUGCUGGGAUUACAGGUGUGAGCCACCGCGCCCGGCCGAGAAUGACAUCUUAAAGCCACCAUUGCGUUCCUCAUUUGUGAACUGUCUUCUCAUAUUUUAAGUCAAGUCUAUAAGAUCAUUUUUAACCUAAGUUCCAACUUUGUUGGACUCCUUAAAAUAAGCACCCAUGAAAGCCAGCCAGCCCUUCCUCCUUCCCUCACCACCCUCCGUCUCUUCGGCUGCUUGCUCUUUAGUGUAGAUUAGUGGAAGCCAUUCACAGAAUGUAGACUCAUGUAUAGGUCACCGUUUCUUUCCCCCACUAGAAAUCACAUUCACUAAGCAGUGGAUUGAAUUUAAGAGUGCUGCCCCUGCCCGGCGCAGUAGGGCGUGCCUCUAGUUCCAGCUACUCGGGAGUCUGAGGCAGAGGAUGGCAUGUGCCAGGAGUUUGAGGCUGCAGUGCACUAUGCUUGCACCUGUGAAUAGCCACUGCACUCCAUCUUGGGCAACACAGUGAGACCCCCAUCUAUAAAAAGAGAGCACUGCCUGAACCUCGGUGGCACUGGGAAGCUCUGGCCUGAGAGUUAAACACCCAUGCUGAAUGAUACAGUGUGCAUUCUCUCCAGCUGCAAACUUUCUUCAACUUUCCUAAAUUCUUACUAAAUUCAGAGGAAUAGGAUAAAGAUCACUUAGAGAAAGGGUGCUUAUGGACAUAGCCUGAGUUUCCUUUAACCUCUCUGCAAUGGGUGCUUUUAACUAGCUUCUACAUGGCAAGCUGUUUCAGUUUGCAAAAUCACUGCCCAGCAUGUUUGAGGUCAGUUGGCACCUUAAAACACCUGUUCUCCAGCCCUUGGACAGUGGAGAGAAUCUGUAAAAGUGUGACCCCCUCUAAGAUUUCGUUUUAAAUGAUCAGAUUCGGUUCCAGUUUUAUUCUUGUUGAGUUUUUCCCUAUGAAGGCUCCUUUUGAAUGUGUCUUGAGACCCAAAUUGAGCAUGUUGCUGUUAUUCCUGCCCUGCACCUGUGGAGCAGGAGUGGCAGGGCUGGCUGUGCUGGGUUCCAGCUCGCUCCCACCGAGGGACUAGCUUGGCCUUUGCGCUUUGAUUCCAGAUAGUAAGAUGAGUGGAAGUGUUUAUCGAGCAUGCAAAAGAAACCCUCACGGCUAAGGGCUCUGGGAGUUGUGUCUGUGUGACCUGAGAGUGAUCCAUCUCCUGCCUGUGUGAGGUAGCAGUGGGCACUUUUCAUUGAGACAAACUCCAGGGUGUCCAGAGGGGGUUCUGCCCCUUGUGAAGGCCCAUUCCUGGCACUUAGAGACAGAAAGAACUCAGCAAUCUUUCGUUCUAGUUAUAUUCGGUCUUUGAAACUGACAAUCUUUGAAAUGUGAAUACUGUAACAAUAUGUUUUCUUGGAUUGUUGUCUUUAAAAAGGAUUUUUGUGAAGCAAUUGAUUUAUCAAAGCAAAAAAAUUAAAAAUAGAAACUUGCUUUAUGGAUGUUUUAUUUUAUAAAGCUCAUGUCACCAAAAGCUGCUUCUCCAUUUUAUGUAAAACAUUGAGAAUGUUUUCAUGUUUUCUGGUGACAUGUAGGGUCUGUAGUCACCCCUGCAUAUUGAGAAACUAGGACCACACUGCAUCGGACUAGUCAGGUCCAUUUACAUGUCCAAGAAUCUUUUCUUAAAUUCCUUACUUUGUUCAUUCAUUGGCUGUUCAGGCAGAAAAUGGAAACAGGUAGCUUUUAUGUUUUUUAUUAUAGUUUUCCACAAAUCUAAUUAUUUUGAUAGUUACAAGAAGAUAAUGAUUCAUCAGUAAGCUAACAUAAUCCCUUUCAUAGUUCAUAUU